AAAGGGCUGGACGCUCACCCAAGAAGGGGACCCCGGCCUGACCUCUCUCGGAAUUCAAAAAAAUCUAAGGCUCAGAGAGGGAAUGGGAGCUGGCUCUUCCCUCUGUGUUUAGCAUCCACGUUUUUUGGCGGUCUGGCUGAAACCAGCCCACCCUAGUUCGGGCGCCAGAGCAACGCAGUUCCGAGGGCAGAUCUCCAAGGGGCGGAGGCAGAGCCGCGGGUGAGAGGCUUCCGCGCCGACUUCGGGUUUGCACUCCCCGGAGCCAGAACUCCGUGGCGGCUCCGGGCCUCCGUGGAUCCGAGCAGAGACUGGCUGCCCGCCUGCCACUCGCAGGCUGGGAAAACGCCAGCCGGUGCCUCGCCGGGAAAGUUCUCGGCAAAGCUGGGGAUGAGCCCUCAGCAGGGCAGGCUCCCGGUGCAGCGCGCCCCCAUCCAUUGCCCGCGCGCAAGAACCCGGAAUGGGCCCCACCUGGGCCGGGACUCGGGCGUGCGAUCCCGAGGGCGCCCUGGGGACCACGCAUCGGGUGGGGACCCUGGCCGAGGGCGUGAGCUGACUCAGUUUUUAAAAACUCGCUUCCUCCUUCCCUACUUGUGCCGGUCACUCACCUCGCUGGGAACCAGCCCAGGGCAGAAGGGGGAGAGGGAGGCGGUGGCCUCCCCAGGAAGGAGGAGAGGUGGAUCUUUAACUCAAGACUAGCAUGAAGAGUUGCCUUCUGGCCUGCCCUGAGUCUCCUCAAAUAACAACAGGCCCUUCCACCGCAGCCAUCCGCACGGGAGGCCUCGCGAUUGCUCGGAACCAUCCCGCAGGAGUUCAGCUGAUAUUUUCUAGUGUGGGGCGAGAGAUUUUGUGGAGCGCAUUUAAGGGGUUUUUGUUGUGACUGCUGCCUUGUAUACAUUUAUUUUCUUUCUUGGAACUGGGCCUCGCCCUCCUCCCACUGACAUGAUGGCCCAGUCCAAGGCCAAUGGCUCGCACUAUGCGCUGACCGCCAUCGGCCUGGGGAUGCUGGUCCUUGGGGUGAUCAUGGCCAUGUGGAACCUGGUACCCGGCUUCAGCGCGGCCGAGAAGCCAACAGCUCAGGGCAGCAACAAGACCGAGGUGGGUGGCGGCAUCCUCAAGAGCAAGACCUUCUCUGUGGCCUACGUGCUGGUCGGGGCCGGGGUGAUGCUGCUGCUGCUUUCUAUCUGCCUGAGUAUCAGGGAUAAGAGGAAGCAGCGGCAGGGCGAGGACCUGGCCCAUGUCCAGCACCCGACAGGCGCUGGGCCUCACGCCCAGGAGGAAGACAGCCAGGAGGAAGAAGAGGAGGAUGAGGAGGCUGCCUCAAGGUACUAUGUUCCCAGCUACGAGGAAGUGAUGAACACAAACUACUCAGAAGCAAGGGGAGAGGAGCAGAACCCGAGGUUGAGCAUCUCUCUCCCGUCCUAUGAGUCACUGACGGGGCUCGACGAGACCACCCCCACAUCCACCAGGGCUGACGUGGAGGCCAGCCCUGGGAACCCCCCUGACAGGCAGAACUCUAAGUUGGCCAAACGACUGAAACCGCUGAAAGUUCGAAGGAUUAAAUCUGAAAAGCUUCACCUCAAAGACUUUAGGAUCAACCUCCCAGACAAAAACGUCCCUCCUCCCUCGAUAGAGCCUUUGACUCCUCCACCGCAGUAUGAUGAAGUCCAGGAGAAGGCCCCCGACACCCGGCCGCCCGACUGAAUGGCCCCACUUGAGCCACGCUCCCUCCUGUCUCUCACACCUUUCACCCCCAAGACUCUAACAAAGCCACAUGAGCCACAGUUGAGAAGCGGAGGGGCCAGCUGUGCAUGGAGCCAUUUGGAUGGCGGCGGGCGGGGGGGGAUUCUCUGUAUCAGGAGUGACUUUGUUGCCCCACACAGCCUCCUGCUGCAGGUGCUUUGGAAAGAGAUGCUGCCUUGGAGCUGGUGAAUCUGUGGACCACAUUCAAGGGUGUGGCACAGGCAUCUUCCCAUCCUUUUCACUCCGAAUCGCUGGCGACACAUUCUCCUUUCCAGCUAGGAAAGGGUUCCUCGCGGCUGGUUUAGAUUGUGGUUGUUUGUUUUGCUUCUACUAAGACUGUUUUGUUUCAAAAAGGAAACAAGUUUUGUGUUUGCUGUCUACGCUGGAGUCCUGAACUGUGGGUAGAAAACACGACCUGGCUUUGUAGAAAGGACACAGGGCUGUUUUAUGAACUAAGCGGUGAGGCUCAGGUGGCGGCUCUCGCAGAGCCCCUGAUGCUGUUGUUCUUUGAGGGCUUAAGGCCUGAUGAACGUAGGCACGUGAUGCAUAAUAGUCUUCAAUGGUACACUUAACUAGUCUCUUCUGUGUAACAGCAAAAAAAAAAAAAAAAAGAAGAAGAAAGAAAACUGUAGGAAAUGUUCUUUUUGAAAUGCCAUGCAAUGGAGCUUUUUGUAAUAAAAUAUUUUAUAUGUAGUA